AGGAGAGGAAAGACCUGAGAACUCGGUGCGGGGAGGCUGCUCCCUUUGCGGGGGAGCCGUUCCCCGUUCCCCCAGUGAGCUUCCCCAGCCGGAGGGUCUGGGACGGACGGAGGAGGCUGUCUCGCUGUGGAGGGUGGGCCCGGCCUCCGGGGUCUCCUUUCAGAGUCCGUUUCAAAUGGCGUGGGCAGAACUCCUGAGUGUGUGCAGGUGGACGGCGGCCAGGUGCCCCUGGCCACAGAAAAGAGAUGGUGGAUUUCUUAACUAUUUUGGGAGGGACUCCCCAGAGAAGGAAGAGGCUGAGAAGGAGGCCCCCCGGGGCUGGAGCCCCCUCUGGCCUACAGUGCCCCCCCAUCUCCUCUCUGGGGAUCUGAAAUGGGCUCCUCAGCCACCCAGGCAACUUGGCCCCACCACGGGGCCUGGCUGGCCGCCUUCCCUAGGAGUCACGAGAGGACAUUUAGGGGCGUCUUUGAAAAUCACCUCAGUGCAAAGACUGCAGAAGAAACAGCAAAGAGCCAUCCCCCAGCAUUCAGGAUCUCAGAGACCGUGAAGAUGUAGAUAUAGAGGUGGCUGACCGUAGUAGAGAUGGCAGCACCCAACACGGGGCGGUGUGUCAGAGUUUUCCCAUUGGAGGUGCGGGGGACAGAGCCCAGAAGGCCUGGGUCCAGCUGCAGCCGUGUGCCCAUCAGGAGACCGCGGGGUCGGCACUGCCCCUGGCUCUAAGCAGCCCGUGUCCUGGGAAGAGCUUUGUUCUUCCAUCAAUCCCAGUGGGCCUUUCUCCCUUUGUCCUUCCCCUCCUUCAAGGUGAGAGGAAGGACGAAGCUCGGGGCACAGUUGUGGAUGCUGUGCUGGAGCCAUGGGGACAGCUGCCAGCCCAGGCCCACGGCCACUUAGCCAAGAGGCUGAAAUCCAGACGGCUCUGAAACCCCAAAGUUUUAGCCCAAGUUCGACACCAGAAUUCAGUUGGCAGCAAGUCCCGUCCCGCAUGGACGUGAGACUCUUCUCAUCUUUAUUAAUCCUACUUCUGGGAUUAUUUAUAUACACUUCCUGCUGGGAAAUUCUUCAGGCCGCCCCCAGCCACAGCCUCUGUGUCCACCAUUUCCCUGCUCUAAAAUCUGAAGAUCCUUAAUCCUGGCCUGCAUCUGGCUCCUGGGCUGACGGGGAAGGGAUUCUGUGCCUGUUUCCUUGGGCAGGAAAGCUGGAAGGCCACGGCCCAGCCAGGAGUGGGGGGCCUCUGGGCCUGCAGUCACUCCCAUCCCUGGAAGAGGGGUGCCGUUGGGGAGGACACCUUGCCUGGUGAGAGGUGCACUGCUUUGCUCAGCUCCCCUUUCGCUCUCUAGUUAAAAACAGUUACCACCUGGCUGCAUGCUGCAGCCUCUCCUUUGAGGUCAUCCUGUCCACACACAUGUGCUGGGCUCAACCUCCUGCUCUUGGCGUCUAGGGGCAGGCCUGGAGGGUCUCCCCAGGGUGGAAGCACCUGCCAACUCAGCCCUAGGGGCCACCUUCAGACUUAGCGGGGUGCUGUCCAUGAAGGGCCUCUCUGUAUCUGUGCCCCUACACUCCAGAAACCAGGACAGCCGCCCUCCCUUCCCUCAGUCUCGGGGUCCUUGUCCUGGAGCUGUAUUGGACGUCAGUGGGACCCAUUCUGGCCAUUACCCCAGGUCCCCAUUGCAGCAGCUCCUCAUGGGAAAGGCUGGGUGGGAUAGGAAGGGAGUGUGCUGCGUGGCGGCCGUGGGUCGGCCCGGAGUGUGAAGACCCGUGCACGCGGCAGGCACCGAGCUUGCCGACUGCAUGCCCGCGUGGGUGGCCCUCCCGGGCUGCCGGCACCUCCGUCUCCCUGGAGAAGCUGUGCUGCGGCUCCUACCGUGCCAGCUCGCGGUGCGCUGGUGGCGGUGCUCCUCUUCGCCUUGGUAACUGCAAUGCUGGGAGGCUUGAGCUGCUCUAAAAGCAGGGCUGUGGGAUAUGUGGGCUGGGUGUGCGCCGUGGAGAAGCCUGCAGGGGGAGGAUCCCAGCUACAUCUACCUUCCCUGUCUGUCCCCAGGGCGCAGACAAGUGACAGGGAUGGGUUUGUUUUUCAGUGGGGCCAGGAGGGCAGGAGGCCAGGUGACCCAUGGAGAGCCACCCGAGGGGGAAGCUGCCAUGUCUUCAUGGUGCCCACUCUGCCCCCUGAGUUUGGAGUCCUAAAUCUGAGUGUAGACUUGGAGCCUGGUGUGUAGCCCUGAGCCUCUCUGUCCAUCCACCCACAGGAAACCCCAAGCUCAGGCCACCACUGGGCCCCAGGGCCACCAGGUGAGGCAGCAGCCCUCUCCCGAGGUCUCCGUGACAUACCAGAGUCAGGACAGCCCCACCCUGUGCCUAUCUCCGCUGGUGCAGGCUGUGUUCCCCCAGCCCCCGCUAGAUCUGCCUCCCUUGUACAUCCUGACCUGAGGAAGUGAGGGGCCCUCCAGACCCCAGAGUCUGGCAUGAAGCGCACGCCCCCGCACUCUGGCCCUUCCCAUCUGUUCACGGUGGGAAAACGACCGGGGGCUCUCCUAGGUGAGAAAUGGCGUGGGGGUGGGAGCCUGCUUCCUUCUCGCCCCCAGGAGAUGGCAAAGGUGCCUCCAGGUGAGCUUCGUGGCGGGGGCUGCUCCUGGCCUUGCCUUCGUGCCCCCCCACAUGUGCCACCACCCUGAGAUGGGCAAGAGAUGUGGCCCAGGAAGGACGGUGUCUCCUGUGGCCUCAUUCCAGGCAGGCUAGAUGGCAGCUGGGCUGGUCCAAAAAUAAAGCCUCACUAGAGCCCUUUGCGUCCGACCUUCAAGGCAACUGCCAUUUGCAUUUUUAAUUGGCCGGGACUUAAUUUGAUUCCAUCUUAUACUUUGUUACCAAAGUGCCUGCUCCUCCUUAGCCCUGUGCCGGGCCACUCCUGGGGGUCCCGUGGGCGCGGGGUCCUGGGUCUGGAUGGACAGCAGCCCUGGAUGCUGCCUCCAGCUGGCUCCUGCCAGAGUUGGGCCACCACAGUCGUCCAGGACAGAUUGGGGUUGGCAGAAUCUGGUUAGCUAAGGAACGUUUGGUUCAAAGUCCAAAUCUUUGAAAGGCCAGUGUGUAAAACAAGAAGAAAAGUGGUUCUGAUGGAAAGGGAGAGGGCCUCAGCCCCCGACCCCGCUGCUGCUGCCUCCCAAACCCCGGUGGUCCUCAGGGGGCCCAGGACGCACCUGAGGAUAAAGUGUAUGGAGCAGAGUCAAGGCUGGAUGCAGGGAGAGGCAGGGAGAGUGUCCACCUCCCAGCAUCCUUCCCAGUGUUUCUCUGGAAUUGCGGGUUUAAGAUUUGGACCUGCUCAUGCAGCUCCCCGGCUGGACUUAGCCUGAGGCACCAGACCUCUGUGCCCUGCCCCUUGCCUCUCCCUUGGGAAUCCAAGGACUCAAGAGGGCUGGAGCCGGAGAGACAGACAAGCAGAGUAGGCUGCAGGUGAUCUGUGUGGGGCACUGGGAGGGUGCUGCACGGGGUGGGGCUGGUGGCCCGGCCUCAGCUUGACUGUGCCAGACAGGCAGUGUGGAGGGGUGCCUCGAGCCCAGGUCGCAGUCUCUGAGGGAGCAGGAGGCCAAGGGCUGUGGCCCCCACCGUGAGGAGGGGAGGGGCAGUCAGUUGCGUCCUGGGGAGCCAGGCGUGGAGGAGGCCUGGGACUGUGCUCUUCUCUUGGUGGCCUGUGGAGUAGCCCAGCAUAGGGCACCCGCUUGAGGCUGUAUCUGAACUGGGGUCAAAUCUGUCUCUAGGCUUGCUGUGGGGGAGGCCACUGACUCAGGUCCCGGCCCCUCAACUCUCCUGGAGGGCUCGGGCCAGGCUCGGGCCUGGCGACCUGGAGGACAUGUCUGAAGCCACCCCCUUGGAUAGAAAUGAUUCUGAGAAUACAGGGGGGUUAAUCUCAAGGCCCCACCCCUGGGACCAAUCCCCAUCCUGUGUGCAGGAGGACAGGUAUGACAAUCACCACAAACUGGACGGCUUGAAACAACAGACGCCUAUUCUCUCGCAGCUCGGGAGGCCAGGAGCCUGAAAUCAAGGUGUGGGUGGGGCUCGUUCCCCUGGAGGCUCUGAGGGAACCUCCGUCCCUGGCCUGUCUCCAGCUCCGGCGGUGGCUGGAAACCCUGGCCUCCCCUGGCCUGUGGACGCCUCACCCCAAUCUCUGCCUCCUCUGUCCCCAGGCUUCUUCCCUCUUCUCUUCUAAGGACACCAGUCCUUGGGUUUAGGGCCCACCCAAUCCAGUAUGGCCUCAUCUUAACUAAUUACCUCUGCAAAGACCUUAUUCCCAAAUAAGCUCACAUUCUGAGGCUCUGGGUGGAUGUGCAUUUUGGGGGACGCUGUUCAACCCAGUGCAGGUGAGCAGAUGGGGGCCGGGGGGGUGCUGGGGUGCUCUGGGCUCUGGCAGCAUGGUGUGUAUGGGGAGGAGAUGCCUCCCUCAAGCCUGGGCGUCCCCAUGGCCCUGCUGUCUACCCCGAGCUGCUCCGAGGUUGAGCUAAACCACAGAAGCACAUGGCCAUUUGGGGAUCUGGAGCCCACCCUGGGCCUUCCUGGGAGGAGACAGAGAGUAGGAGGCUGUGGGCCCGGGUUUUGGGGCCCUGUCCUCUUCCUGUCCCUGCCCCUUGCCUCCUCCUCACAUUCCUCUUCUCCAAACCGUCUAAUGGGGGAAGCUUCGCCCUCAGAAGCCGACAGGGAGACCUCUUUGGUGAGGGACCCCAGGGGUGGAGACCCGAGGCCGGCCUCCGCGGGCUGGUUGAGGAGGGAGGCUGUUAGCCUGGGAGCUUGGCCCACGCUGGGGGGCUCUGUCCAACCCAGGGCCACCUCCCUCAAAGCCAGGAGGGCUAAGUGGGCACUGAGGCCGGAGGAGGAAGCCAGGUCAGGGCCAGUGGAAGAGGCUGAGGACCUCCCGGGGUUCCCUGUGUCCAGCCAGAGGCUUGGGGACUGGCCAGGCCCCCACCUGCAAGGGCUCCCACAGUGGCCCCCCAUGCCCUGGCCCAGGUGCCCAGAACAGUGCUGCAUCCCCAGGAAGGGACCCAGGCUCAGUGGAAUUAAAUUAAGUCCUGGCCUGUCUGACCGGUGGCUUUGCAUCCCCAGAGCGAUGAAUGACAUCGGCGACUACGUGGGCUCCAACCUGGAGAUCUCCUGGCUCCCCAACCUGGACGGGCUGAUAGCCGGCUACGCCCGCAACUUCCGGCCUGGCAUCGGAGGCCCCCCCGUGAAUGUGGCCCUUGCCCUGGAGGUGGCCAGCAUCGACCACAUCUCAGAGGCCAACAUGGAGUACACCAUGACGGUGUUCCUGCACCAGAGCUGGCGGGACAGCAGGCUCUCCUACAACCACACCAACGAGACCCUGGGUCUGGACAGCCGCUUCGUGGACAAGCUGUGGCUGCCCGACACCUUCAUCGUGAACGCCAAGUCGGCCUGGUUCCACGACGUGACGGUGGAGAACAAGCUCAUCCGGCUGCAGCCCGACGGCGUGAUCCUGUACAGCAUCCGAAUCACCUCCACUGUGGCCUGCGACAUGGACCUGGCCAAAUACCCCAUGGACGAGCAGGAGUGCAUGCUGGACCUGGAGAGCUACGGUUACUCAUCGGAGGACAUCGUCUACUACUGGUCGGAGAGCCAGGAGCACAUCCACGGGCUGGACAAGCUGCAGCUGGCGCAGUUCACCAUCACCAGCUACCGCUUCACCACGGAGCUGAUGAACUUCAAGUCCGCUGGCCAGUUCCCACGGCUCAGCCUGCACUUCCACCUGCGGAGGAACCGCGGCGUGUACAUCAUCCAAUCCUACAUGCCCUCCGUCCUGCUGGUCGCCAUGUCCUGGGUCUCCUUCUGGAUCAGCCAGGCGGCGGUGCCCGCCAGGGUGUCUCUAGGCAUCACCACGGUGCUGACGAUGACCACGCUCAUGGUCAGUGCCCGCUCCUCCCUGCCACGGGCAUCAGCCAUCAAGGCACUGGACGUCUACUUCUGGAUCUGCUAUGUCUUCGUGUUUGCCGCCCUGGUGGAGUACGCCUUUGCUCAUUUCAACGCCGACUACAGGAAGAAGCAGAAGGCCAAGGUCAAGGUCUCCAGGCCGAGGGCAGAGAUGGACGUGAGGAACGCCAUUGUCCUCUUCUCCCUCUCUGCUGCCGGCGUCACGCAGGAGCUGGCCAUCUCCCGCCGGCAGCGCCGCGUCCCGGGGAACCUGAUGGGCUCCUACAGGUCGGUGGGGGUGGAGACAGGGGAGACGAAGAAGGAGGGGGCAGCCCGCUCAGGAGGCCAGGGGGGCAUCCGUGCCCGGCUCAGGCCCAUCGACGCAGACACCAUUGACAUUUACGCCCGCGCUGUGUUCCCUGCGGCGUUUGCGGCCGUCAAUGUCAUCUACUGGGCGGCAUACGCCAUGUGAGCACAGGACUCAGGCCACCCUCGCUUGUCCUGGCGCCCGGCGGCAGCUGCCCAGAAACUUCCUGGGAGAAAGAGCCCUCGGGCUGCCUUCCCCUCUGCGUGUUUCGAAGUGGGAUGACAGUCGGCCACGGAAAACAAGAGGAAGCCUCGGCCUCCCUGAGCUCUGACCCCAGCCUCACCCGAAAGGCCAGCCUGGGGCUCUCCGGCAGGCAGCCCGAGACCUGCACAGAUGAAGGAGCAGAGGUUCUGACCGAGAGGCUGAGCCAGGCCGGGGUCUGGGCCCUUCAGGGAGCCGCGGAUUUUUAUGUUCAGAAAGUGAUCCUGGUUUCUAGGUCUUUGCUCUGCAGGAUCGGGAUCAGAGCGUGGGAGGAGGUGGGGGUGGACGUCCAUCCGGUGAACAGUGAAGGCGUUUGUGAGGUCUUUCUGGUCCCAGCAUGAAAUAAAGCCUUGGCCUGGGGGCCGCUUCAUUCUCCCUCA